CCUGCUCUAGCGGGCCGCGUAGCGGACAUGGCGGGCUCCCGGCUCCCGCGGCAGCUCUUCCUCCAGGGCGUGGCGGCCGUCUUCAUGUUUGCUUUCGCUUCCCUCUACACGCAAAUCCCAGGUGAAGGCACCCAGGGUGGGACACCCCCAGCCUCGGCGCGGGACCCUAUGUCCUCUUUUCUCUGUGCCCGGCACUCACGCAGUCCGGGGUUGGGAGUGAGGGCCAGGCCUUGGCGUGGGGUAGGGGGCGGCGGUUCGUGUCCUGCAGGCCGCUGUGGGGGUAGGAAGGUGUGCGGUGAUCCAUUUCCCGUAAGGCUCUGGACUCUGACCUGGGGUGGGGGACAGAACUCUGAGAGAGGUGGGAGAGAGGCUUCCUCCCAGACCUGGUGGGACAGGUAGGAGAUCGGGCUGAGACCUGGAAGAGGGCAGUGGGCUCUGCUGGGUGGGAGGCCCUGACUCAGGUAGUUGAGCAGGCCUCUAGCCCUGGGACGGGGUUUUGACAGGUCCCGACCUGGGGGACGGGCUCUGGAGGGACUGCAGACUCUGACCUAGGGAUGGAGGUAUCCGCAUGCUCUGACCUAGGCUGGGGGAUCUGCAGGCCCUGACUCAGAGGUAGUCUAGUCUGCAAGGGCUGUCCAGGGCCUGGCCAUGACAUGCCCUCCCACAGGCCUGUAUGGCCCCGAGGGCAUCCUACCUGCAAGGAGGACGCUGCGGCCUCAGGGCAAGGGGCGCUGGCAGCAGCUGUGGGAGACCCCGACGCUGCUGUGGGAAGCGCCGAGACUGGGGCUGGACACGGCCCAGGGCCUGGAGCUGCUGAGCCUGCUGGGUGCACUAGUGGCCCUGGGAGCCCUGCUGCUGAGCCCACUGCGCCACCCUGUCAUCUACUUGCUGCUUUGGGCCGCCUACCUGUCAGCCUGCCAGGUGGGCCAGGUGUUCCUUUAUUUCCAGUGGGACUCCCUGCUGCUAGAGACUGGCUUCCUGGCCGUGCUGGUGGCCCCGCUGAGGCCAGCCUCCCACCGCAAGGAGGCCCCCCAGGGCAGGCAGGCAGGGGCCCUGCCCCACGAAGACCUCCCCUUCUGGCUGCCCUCACCUACCACUACGAGACCCAGUGCCUGCCCACGCCCGCCGCCUGGUUCGCACACCACCUGCCGGUCUGGCUGCACAAGCUCAGCGUGGUGGCCACCUUCCUAAUUGAGAUCGCUGUGCCGCCCCUGUUCUUCGCCCCCAUUCGACGCCUGCGCUUGGCUGCUUUCUACUCGCAGGUGCUGCUGCAGGUCCUGAUUAUCAUCACCGGCAACUACAACUUCUUCAACCUGAUGACGCUGGUGCUUACCACUGCGCUGCUGGACGACCAGCACCUGGCUGCUGAGCCUGGCCACGGCAGCCGCAAGAAGACGGCCACCUCCUGGCCCAAGGCCCUGCUGGCCACCCUGUCGCUGCUGCUGGAACUAGCCGUCUACGGGCUUCUGGCCUAUGGCACUGUGCACUACUUUGGCCUGGAGGUUGACUGGCAGCAGCGCACCAUCCACUCCAGAACCACUUUCACCUUCCACCAGUUUUCUCAGUGGCUGAAGACACUGACGCUGCCCACUGUGUGGCUGGGUGUGGCCUCCCUGGUCUGGGAGCUGCUGAGUGCCCUGUGGAGGUGGACCCAGGUGCGGGGCUGGCUACGGAAGCUCAGUGCUGUAGUCCAACUGUCCCUUGUGGGCACUGCGACCGUGGCCUUGUUCCUGAUUAGCCUGGUGCCGUACUCCUACGUGGAGCCCGGGACCCACGGGCGCCUCUGGACCGGGGCCCACCGCCUGUUUGGUGCCGUGGAGCACCUACAGCUGGCCAACUCCUACGGCCUCUUCCGCCGCAUGACUGGGCUUGGUGGACGGCCUGAGGUGGUGCUGGAGGGCAGUUACGACGGCCACCACUGGACGGAGAUCGAGUUCAUGUACAAGCCUGGGAACCUGAGCCGGCCGCCCCCGGUUGUGGUGCCCCACCAGCCACGCCUGGACUGGCAGAUGUGGUUUGCAGCCCUGGGCCCACACACGCACAGCCCGUGGUUCACAAGCCUGGUCUUGCGCCUGCUGCAGGGCAAGGAGCCAGUGAUCCGCCUUGUCCAGAGCCAAGUGGCCAGGUAUCCCUUCCACAAGCAGCCGCCCACCUACGUCCGAGCCCAGCGCUACAAGUACUGGUUCUCCCAGCCUGGGGAGCAGGGCCAGUGGUGGCGGCGCCAGUGGGUGGAGGAGUUCUUCCCAUCCGUGUCCCUGGGGGACCCCACGCUGGAGACGCUGCUCAGGCAGUUUGGACUACAGGAGAAAAGCCCACCUCGCACCCGCAGCGCCAACAGCACCCUGGCCCAGGCCCUCCACUGGACUCGCUCUCAGCUGUCUCCCCUGGAGGCCCCCGCCCUGCUCUGGGGGCUCCUCAUGGCCGUGGGGGCUGUCAGAUUUGUGCAAGCCCUGCUAGCACCCUGUUCUCUCCGGUCCUCCCCGCUGGCACCAGUCAGCGGGGAGAAGCGCAGGCCAGCCUCCCAGAAAGACUCCGGAGCUGCCUCCGAACAGGCCACCGCAGCCCCCAACCCCUGCUCCAGUAGUUCGAGGACCACCCGGCGAAAGAAGUAGCUGUGUUCUCCCAGCUGCACGUCCUGAGAGGGCCAGGUCGCCGGGAGUGCUCUGGCCUCCGGCAGGACAGGACCCAGCCACUGUGCCUUAGCUGACCCUGCAGGGCCAGGCACAGGUUGGGGGGCUGCCCCUGGGGUUUGCAGGGUGCUGCAUUGAGGGCUCCAGGCCCCACCCCCACGCCAGCCAUGCCCCUCCCCAGGACUCCCACUAUUGCCUCUGUGAUUGGCCCAGGAGGAAAACACGACCAAGCUCAAGACCCUUCCCCUGCCCUGGGCUGUGGGGGUCUGAGUCUAGAGCCCCCAACCCUAGGCCCCGUGCCAGAGGGGAAGAGGCUGACUCCCAGGGGAAGAGGGGAAGCACUGUCAUCUUCCACGUCAUCUUCACACCAGCCCAUCCUGCCCUUUAGAUCUGGGCACCAAUAAAGGCGUCUUUUGUGCUUGGC